UUUGAGGGGAUCUUGAGGGUGAGGCUGCCCAACGAGGACGGGGCUGAGGUGUUGAAGUAACAAACACUGAGUUAGAACUCAGAGCAAAUCGGAAACAGCUGGUGGCUGAGCUGGGCGAAAAGCUGUAGUUUUUAAAACAUGGUGGCCAAUCUCGCCAUUGCUGCCACUGAGAUGCAGGGUGUCUGUCCCCUUGCUGUGGAUCUGGGUUACUUCCUGACUGCCUUGAUUGGUGGAAUGUGGUGGGUGUGAGGCUGAGUGACCCCCAAUGUGGCUUCCCCAUUGUUCACCAGGAUGCUGGCUCUGGGAGCCCUGUGAUGCCAAGGAAGGAGUUGGCCCUUUGGCAGCCAUGCUGUGAGGAAACCCAAGCUCCACAGGCAGCCAUGGGAGCUCCAGUGGGCAGCCCUGGUAUUCAGUCCCCUCCACUCAGGGCCCUGAUAAGUGAGGGGACAGGCCUUCCAAGGACUGUAGCUGUAGCCCUUGGUAAUUAGGUGUGUCAGCUUUGGUGUCCUUGGACAUUGGAGCAGAGAUGAGCUGACUGAAGCUGGGGCCCGCUGAGGCUCCUCACCCACAGAAUUGGGAGUGUAGUAACAUGUUGCAGGCUGCUGAGUUCAGGGUAACAUGCAACACAGCAGCAGUGACAGGAACAAAAGCGGUGGCUGCCCAAGGAGGGGGAAGGAAGGGCCUUGGGGUGGGGUGGGGUGGGGUGGAGGAUGAGGGGGCCAUAGGACUCAGGUUUUGGGUGGGAGAGUGGAGUGUGAACAAGAGGCAGACCCCUAACAAGGGUGCAGUGAGGAUGAUUCAUUUCAUCUCAUUCCGCACAUUUUCAUAGUCUGUGUAUUGGGGGCUUUCUUGCUUUCUCUGUAAAUGAACCAUGAAGGAAACAAUCCCUUUUCAUAGGCGCACAGGGGACAUAGGGAUGAAUGUCUGGUAGCUGCCAUAAAAAGUACCACACACUGGGUGGUUUCCAACAACAGAAACUUAUUCUCCCAGUUCUGGAGGUCAGAAGUAAAAAUCAAGGUGUCAGCAGGGCCACACUCCCCUGAGGCUCUAGGGGGGCCUCCGUCCUGCUUCUUCCCUCUUGUGUGGCCCCAGUGUCCCUUGGCUUGUGACACAUUGCUCCAGUCUCUGCUCCAACAUCACAUGGCGUCUGCGUCUGUCUUUCCCUCUGAGUGUAUCUAUAAGGGCACUUGUCCCUGGAUUUAGGGCCCACUCAGAUAACCCAGGGAGAUCUCAUCCUGAGAUUCUUACAUCUAGAAAGACCCUUUUUGCAAACAAGAUUGCAUCUCUUCAACCUGUUACAGCACACAAGAAGGCAAUUGAAAUACUGCGCGGGCUGAGCUGGUGGCCCUGGUGGGCGGAGACAGGGCUGGCAGGCUUUCACCUUCUCCAGGAUAUAUUUCAGCAGGGCUUUAUCAGCAGGAAAAUGGAAACCACAGCUGCUUUUUGCCUUUGUGGGAAGCUGUAGAAAUAAGAGUACAGUGGAAACUCUCUGCUUCGUAAAAUAACUUCAUGUUGACUCAGAGGGGAAACAGGAAAGGUGCCUUCUAUCUUUUUUAUGCGAGUUUUUCUCUCUGUUGGUGGGGCCUUUGCUUUUAAGGAGUGUUUCUACAAGAAUACUUGUUGGAUAUUUAGUGUGAACAGGAAGUAAGAUGUGCUGACUAACUUUUCCAUUAUUUUAAUGGCAUUUUUAUUGCUCAGAAAAUGAAGACAGAAAGCAAAGAGUGAACGCUUUCAUUGUGCUGGGUAAAUGCCAUAAACAACCUGCCUUUCUGAAUUUUUUUCUCUGCGAUUUUCAGAUGCACACACAUGCGUGCAUGCAUAAGUACACACACAUCCAUAGAGGGGGUGUUUCCCCAAAGUCGCGGUCAUGCCACGCAGAGGUAUGCACCUUGCUUUAUUUGCUCACCACUGUGUCAUAGAUGUGUAUGUUCUGCAGUGUGCUACGAAGCCAUGUGUGCCCUUGUGUGUGCUGUGUGUCCCUGGGGCCUUCAGUGGAGGUCUCUCCAGUCUGCCACACCCUUGACUGUUUUCCUUGGUGUACAUUACUCUUGUCAAGGCAUUGAUUAGCAGGACAUGUGAUGGCCCCUGUGAAUGGUGGAGCCCAGAAAAUGAAAUUGGCAGUGUUUUAGUAGGCCGUGUGUGUUUGUGUGUGUGUGGGGGGGUGCAUGCAUGUGUGUAUGUGAAUGUGUGUGAGCAUUUGUGUGUGUGUGUGUGUACGUGCAUGUACCUUGUGCAUAUAUGCAUGUGUGUGUGAGUGCCUGCCUGCACAUGUGUGCUCAUAGGUUCCAGAAUAGCAGUGCACAGCAUGCUGGAAGUCUGCAUUCUGGGAGAGUUUCUUGGAUUUAGGAGUCUCUUCUCAUUAGGAGGCUUACUGAACUUAUUUUACGGAAGUCUUAGUUGUAUUUUUAGCCAAAAGAUAAAACUCGCCCCACUCUCCUCCAUGCCUCCAGCUUGUCUAAAGUGAAAUGGCCUGGGGAGAAUUUGACAUGGUAGUACAGUGAUGUGGUGUGUUUCUCUGGGGUCAGAUAUGUCGGCUCUCCUAUCCCUGGACAGGUCAGCCCAGUAUCCCAGCCAAAUAUUGUGUAUGUGCCUAGAUCCUUCACAGGCAUGACUUUUUGUUGGUGCCAUGUGGUCAUGGGGGCUUCCUUCCGCAGUCAGGUUCUGCUCCGAAGUGGGGAUUGGAGGCAUCUCUGGAGCCUGGCGUGAUACCUUUGCCAUGUCCCUGAUUGAUUGUGUCGGUCAGGGUCCCCCACAGAAGUGAAACUAAUGGGUGUGUGCAUGUGUAUGCGUGUGUAGACAUUACAAGGAAUUGGCUCACCUGAUUGUGGAGAUGCCACGAGUCUAAAAUAUACAGCAGGCUGGAGACCCAGAGAAGAAUUGCAGCUCAAUGGAAGGCUGUCUGGAGGCAGAACUUUCUGCUCUUCUCCUUGGGGGAGGUCAGCCUGUGCUAUUCAUGCCUUCAGCUGAUUGGAUGAGGACCACCCUCAUUACAGAGGGCCAUUUGCUUUACUCAAAGCCUCUGCUUUAAAUGUUGAUCUCAUUAAAAAAGUAAUACCUCCACAGAAGUAUCAAGAAUAAUGAUUGGCCAGAUAUCUGGGUACUGUGGCACAGCCAAGUUGACAUGUGACAUCAGCCAUCACACUGGUCAGUGCUCCCCAGUGCACGGGCCCCGUGGCAUGCUAUGUUUUAUAAACCAGUGUGGGCCCUAGGUAAGGUGUGUGAGCUUGCUCAAGGUGUAUUGUAUGAAGGUGUUGCCCUGCUCCCAGAAGCCUGCCCCAGAGCAGGCAGGGCUUGUUAUUCUUGCCCAGAGAUCAUCGGGCCAGCAUGAGGUGGCCGAAGGUUGGCACUUCUUACAUUCUAAUGGCACCAGGAGCGAGGUCCGGGGCCUUGUGCAAGCUGCGCUCACACCUCAGCCGACCUUCUGCUUCUUAGGAAGGUUGCUUCAUUCCGGUCACCACUGGCCCCAUAUUUAAGCAUCAGUAAUACCUUAGGUGCCUCUGGGGACCAUUCCUGUUGUCCUCCUUCCAAAAACUGCUUCAUUUUCCUUCAAAAUGUGACAUGGCUUGGACAUGCUAGAGGCAUUUAUUAGCAGAAAGCCUGGGAGCUCUGCCUCCAUGAUAUUUUCUUUUUCUGGGAAAAAAAAUAUUUGUGCAAGCCAUGGUCAUAUCAUUGUUUCCCGCUCUCUGUGAGCCUGCUGACAUUGGCCUCCCGUGUGCCUGGCGUGCUCUUAUCAGACCUGUGUGCCAUCCUGUGAAUUCUACCGUAAACAGUCACAGCGAGGCGGGAGAAACACAGCCUGGUGGUCCACGGCAGGCUUGGUCUGGACUGGAUGGGAGCUGCCUGAUGGAUCAGUAGGGGAAUGCAGAGGGGUGCCAGCUCCAGGACUGGUAAAGGUGGCUCUUCUCUUUCUUUUCCAUCAGGUGCAGUGUUGGAGUGAAUGAAUGAUUGAUGGGUGAACAAGUGAGAGAGUGGAGCUGGUCACAGAGGGUGGGCUUGAAAACGAUAAUGAAGUGUACACACUGAAAAAACAAAAAUCACCCACGGGUUCUGAAGCUCAGUGGAGUUCUGCAGACUCUGCUAACACCAGAUAGUGGAAAGAAACCAUGUGCUGAAAUGUUUGACGACACUGAUGGUUUGACUCUGCUAACUGGAAUGGCUUAUUGUGCAAGAAAGUACACCUGGUCGGGUCCUGGGGCUCAUCUCUAGCACCAGCAAAGAUUUCUGAAGACGUCUUUCUAGAAAUGACUGGAAAGUUUCAAGAGGCAUAAGAUACAGCAUUUCUUCUGAGGCCCUGAAGAAGUAUCAAGUGGGCUUUGACAUUGCGGUGGUGAGAGCGACCCCUCCUCACCUGGAGAACUGGGAAAUGUGGAUUCUCAGGGACCGCGCUGUUCACGAGCUCCAGGCUGUGCUGCUGGCCCUGGUCCUGGGGCGCUGAGCCGCAUCUGCAAUAGCACACCUGCCCGGCCACCUGCUGCCGUGAGCCUUUGCUGCUGAAGCCCCUGGGGUCGCCUCUACCUGAUGAGGAUGUGCACCCCCAUUAGGGGGCUGCUCAUGGCCCUUGCAGUGAUGUUUGGGACAGCGAUGGCAUUUGCACCCAUACCCCGGAUCACCUGGGAGCACAGAGAGGUGCACCUGGUGCAGUUUCAUGAGCCAGACAUCUACAACUACUCAGCCUUGCUGCUGAGCGAGGACAAGGACACCUUGUACAUAGGUGCCCGGGAGGCGGUCUUCGCUGUGAACGCACUCAACAUCUCCGAGAAGCAGCAUGAGGUGUAUUGGAAGGUCUCAGAAGACAAAAAAGCAAAAUGUGCAGAAAAGGGGAAAUCAAAACAGACAGAGUGCCUCAACUACAUCCGGGUGCUGCAGCCACUCAGCGCCACUUCCCUUUACGUGUGUGGGACCAACGCAUUCCAGCCGGCCUGUGACCACCUGAACUUAACAUCCUUUAAGUUUCUGGGGAAAAAUGAAGAUGGCAAAGGAAGAUGUCCCUUUGACCCAGCACACAGCUACACAUCCGUCAUGGUUGAUGGAGAACUUUAUUCGGGGACGUCGUAUAAUUUUUUGGGAAGUGAACCCAUCAUCUCCCGAAAUUCUUCCCACAGUCCUCUGAGGACAGAAUAUGCAAUCCCUUGGCUGAACGAGCCUAGUUUCGUGUUUGCUGACGUGAUCCGAAAAAGCCCAGACAGCCCCGACGGCGAGGAUGACAGGGUCUACUUCUUCUUCACGGAGGUGUCUGUGGAGUAUGAGUUUGUGUUCAGGGUGCUGAUCCCACGGAUAGCAAGAGUGUGCAAGGGGGACCAGGGCGGCCUGAGGACCUUGCAGAAGAAAUGGACCUCCUUCCUGAAAGCCCGACUCAUCUGCUCCCGGCCAGACAGCGGCUUGGUCUUCAAUGUGCUGCGGGAUGUCUUCGUGCUCAGGUCCCCGGGCCUGAAGGUGCCUGUGUUCUAUGCACUCUUCACCCCACAGCUGAACAACGUGGGGCUGUCGGCAGUGUGCGCCUACAACCUGUCCACAGCCGAGGAGGUCUUCUCCCACGGGAAGUACAUGCAGAGCACCACAGUGGAGCAGUCCCACACCAAGUGGGUGCGCUAUAAUGGCCCGGUACCCAAGCCGCGGCCUGGAGCGUGCAUCGACAGCGAGGCACGGGCCGCCAACUACACCAGCUCCUUGAAUUUGCCAGACAAGACGCUGCAGUUCGUUAAAGACCACCCUUUGAUGGAUGACUCGGUAACCCCAAUAGACAACAGGCCCAGGUUAAUCAAGAAAGAUGUGAACUACACCCAGAUCGUGGUGGACCGGACCCAGGCCCUGGAUGGGACUGUCUAUGAUGUCAUGUUUGUCAGCACAGACCGGGGAGCUCUGCACAAAGCCAUCAGCCUCGAGCACGCUGUUCACAUCAUCGAGGAGACCCAGCUCUUCCAGGACUUUGAGCCAGUCCAGACCCUGCUGCUGUCUUCAAAGAAGGGCAACAGGUUUGUCUAUGCUGGCUCUAACUCGGGCGUGGUCCAGGCCCCGCUGGCCUUCUGUGGGAAGCACGGCACCUGCGAGGACUGUGUGCUGGCGCGGGACCCCUACUGCGCCUGGAGCCCGCCCACAGCGACCUGCGUGGCUCUGCACCAGACCGAGAGCCCCAGCAGGGGUUUGAUUCAGGAGAUGAGCGGCGAUGCUUCUGUGUGCCCGGAUAAAAGUAAAGGAAGUUACCGGCAGCAUUUUUUCAAGCACGGUGGCACAGCGGAACUGAAAUGCUCCCAAAAAUCCAACCUGGCCCGGGUCUUUUGGAAGUUCCAGAAUGGCGUGUUGAAGGCCGAGAGCCCCAAGUACGGUCUUAUGGGCAGAAAAAACUUGCUCAUCUUCAACUUGUCAGAAGGAGACAGUGGGGUGUACCAGUGCCUGUCAGAGGAGAGGGUUAAGAACAAAACGGUCUUCCAAGUGGUCGCCAAGCACGUCCUGGAAGUGAAGGUGGUUCCAAAGCCCGUAGUGGCCCCCACCUUGUCAGUUGUUCAGACAGAAGGUAGUAGGAUUGCCACCAAAGUGUUGGUGGCAUCCACCCAAGGGUCUUCUCCCCCAACCCCAGCCGUGCAGGCCACCUCCUCCGGGGCCAUCACCCUUCCUCCCAAGCCUGCGCCCACCGGCACAUCCUGCGAACCAAAGAUCGUCAUCAACACGGUCCCCCAGCUCCACUCGGAGAAAACCAUGUAUCUUAAGUCCAGCGACAACCGCCUCCUCAUGUCCCUCUUCCUCUUCUUCUUUGUUCUCUUCCUCUGCCUCUUUUUCUACAACUGCUAUAAGGGAUACCUGCCCAGACAGUGCUUGAAAUUCCGCUCGGCCCUACUAAUUGGGAAGAAGAAGCCCAAGUCAGAUUUCUGUGACCGUGAGCAGAGCCUGAAGGAGACGUUAGUAGAGCCAGGGAGCUUCUCCCAGCAGAAUGGGGAGCACCCCAAGCCAGCCCUGGACACCGGCUAUGAGACCGAGCAAGACACCAUCACCAGCAAAGUCCCCACGGAUAGGGAGGACUCACAGAGGAUCGACGACCUUUCUGCCAGGGACAAGCCCUUUGACGUCAAGUGUGAGCUGAAGUUCGCUGACUCAGACGCAGAUGGAGACUGAGGCCGGCUGUGCAUCCCCGCUGGUGCCUCGGCUGCGACGUGUCCAGGCGUGGAGAGUUUUGUGUUUCUCCUGUUCAGUAUCCGAGUCUCGUGCAGUGCUGCGUAGGUUAGCCCGCAUCGUGCAGACAACCUCAGUCCUCUUGUCUAUUUUCUCUUGGGUUGAGCCUGUGACUUGGUUUCUCUUUGUCCUUUUGGAAAAAUGACAAGCAUUGCAUCCCAGUCUUGUGUUCCGAAGUCAGUCGGAGUACUUGAAGAAGGCCCACGGGCGGCACGGAGUUCCUGAGCCCUUUCUGUAGUGGGGGAAAGGUGGCUGGACCUCUGUUGGCUGAGAAGAGCAUCCCUUCAGCUUCCCCUCCCCGUAGCAGCCACUAAAAGAUUAUUUAAUUCCAGAUUGGAAAUGACAUUUUAGUUUAUCAGAUUGGUAACUUAUCGCCUGUUGUCCAGAUUGGCACGAACCUUUUCUUCCACUUAAUUAUUUUUUUAGGAUUUUGCUUUGAUUGUGUUUAUGUCAUGGGUCAUUUUUUUUUAGUUACAGAAGCAGUUGUGUUAAUAUUUAGAAGAAGAUGUAUAUCUUCCAGAUUUUGUUAUAUAUUUGGCAUAAAAUACGGCUUACGUUGCUUAAGAUUCUCAGGGAUAAACUUCCUUUUGCUAAAUGCAUUCUUUCUGCUUUUAGAAAUGUAGACAUAAACACUCCCCGGAGCCCACUCACCUUUUUUCUUUUUCUUUUUUUUUUUUUAACUUUAUUCCUUGAGGGAAGCAUUGUUUUUGGAGAGAUUUUCUUUCUGUACUUCGUUUUACUUUUCUUUUUUUUUAACUUUUACUCUCUCGAAGAAGAGGACCUUCCCACAUCCACGAGGUGGGUUUUGAGCAAGGGAAGGUAGCCUGGAUGAGCUGAGUGGAGCCAGGCUGGCCCAGAGCUGAGAUGGGAGUGCGGUACAAUCUGGAGCCCACAGCUGUCGGUCAGAACCUCCUGUGAGACAGAUGGAACCUUCACAAGGGCGCCUUUGGUUCUCUGAACAUCUCCUUUCUCUUCUUGCUUCAAUUGCUUACCCACUGCCUGCCCAGACUUUCUAUCCAGCCUCACUGAGCUGCCCACUACUGGAAGGGAACUGGGCCUCGGUGGCCGGGGCCGCGAGCUGUGACCACAGCACCCUCAAGCAUACGGCGCUGUUCCUGCCACUGUCCUGAAGAUGUGAAUGGGUGGUACGAUUUCAACACUGGUUAAUUUCACACUCCAUCUCCCCGCUUUGUAAAUACCCAUCGGGAAGAGACUUUUUUUCCAUGGUGAAGAGCAAUAAACUCUGGAUGUUUGUGCGCGUGUGUGGACAGUCUUAUCUUCCAGCAUGAUAGGAUUUGACCAUUUUGGUGUAAACAUUUGUGUUUUAUAAGAUUUACCUUGUUUUUAUUUUUCUACUUUGAAUUGUAUACAUUUGGAAAGUACCCAAAUAAAUGAGAAGCUUCUAUCCUUGA